AGAGAGGGGCAGGCUGGUCCCCUGACAGGUUGAAGCAAGUAGACGCCCAGGAGCCCCGGGAGGGGGCUGCAGUUUCCUUCCUUCCUUCUCGGCAGCGCUCCGCGCCCCCAUCGCCCCUCCUGCGCUAGCGGAGGUGAUCGCCGCGGCGAUGCCGGAGGAGGGUUCGGGCUGCUCGGUGCGGCGCAGGCCCUAUGGGUGCGUCCUGCGGGCUGCUUUGGUCCCAUUGGUCGCGGGCUUGGUGAUCUGCCUCGUGGUGUGCAUCCAGCGCUUCGCACAGGCUCAGCAGCAGCUGCCGCUCGAGUCACUUGGGUGGGACGUAGCUGAGCUGCAGCUGAAUCACACAGGACCUCAGCAGGACCCCAGGCUAUACUGGCAGGGGGGCCCAGCACUGGGCCGCUCCUUCCUGCAUGGACCAGAGCUGGACAAGGGGCAGCUACGUAUCCAUCGUGAUGGCAUCUACAUGGUACACAUCCAGGUGACGCUGGCCAUCUGCUCCUCCACGACGGCCUCCAGGCACCACCCCACCACCCUGGCCGUGGGAAUCUGCUCUCCCGCCUCCCGUAGCAUCAGCCUGCUGCGUCUCAGCUUCCACCAAGGGCUUUUUGGAUUUUGGAACUGGGGACUCAAAGUCAAGUGCUUCUUACGGCAUUUAAUAUGGACUGCACACUGUUUUAUCCCAUUAACUCAGCUCGUGUUCAUGCAAGCCCUACAAAGCUGGAGGAAUCAUCAUUGUUCCCAUUUCACAGAUGAGGAAAACAGAGGCGUAAACCGUUGAGUCAUCUGUCCAAAGUUACUGGUUUUGUAACAGCUGGAACCUCAGUAUUUAACAGUUGAGGAAAAUAGUGGCAGAAAACCUGAGUCACAAGCCCGAGGCAAUUCAUCUACAUAGUAGUGGACUCAGGAUUCCAAGCCAGAUAAUCCCGCAUCUUGCAUCCAUGAUCUCACUUCUAGAAGGGGAAGUGAGAGGAGUGGUGGGGUGUCCCAGCUGAGGGAGGGAAAAUGAGACCCAUGCGCCACCCGCCCUCACAAAUCUAGCCCUGCAGCCCCUCUCCAACCUUACCUGGACUCAGAACCAUGCAUCUGGAAAAGCCACAGACACUCGACGCCAGCCUGUGAAAGCAGCCGGGAGGGAGGCUGUAUCCUGCAAAGCCACAGGGAAGGGGCUGCCCAAGACCAUGGGAACCCACCACUUACAUCAGCGUGACCUGGAUGUGAGACACAGAGUCAAAGGAGAUUAUCUGGCAGCUUUAAGAUUGGACUGCCUGACUAUUCACAAUAGCAAAGACUUGGAACCAACCCAAAUGUCCAUCAAUGAUAGACUGGAUUAAGAAAAUGUGGCACAUAUACACCAUGGAAUACUAUGCAGCCAUAAAAACGGAUGAGUUCAUGUCCUUCAUAGGGACAUGGAUGAAGCUGGAAACCAUCAUUCUGAGCAAACUAUUGCAAGGACAGAAAACCAAACACCGCAUGUUCUCACUCAUAGGUGGAAAUUGAACAAUGAGAAUACUUGGACACAGGGAGGAGAACAUCACACACCGGGGCCUGUCGUGGAGUGUGGAGUCGGGGGAGGGGGGGAGGGAUAGCAUUAGGAGAAAUACCUAAUGUAAAUGACAAAUUAAUGGGUGCAGUAAACCAACACGGCACAUAUAUACAUAUGUAACAAAUCUGCACGUUGUGCACAUGUACCCUAGAACUUAAAGUAUAAUUAAAAAAAAAAAAAAAAAAAGAUUUGACUGCCUGGCCAGGCACAGUGGCUCAUGCCUAUAAUCCUAACACUUUGGGAGGCCGAGGCGAGCAGAUUGCCUGAGCUGAAGAGUUCGAGACCAGCCUGGGCAAUAUGGUGAAACCCCGUUUCUACUAAAAUACAAAAAAAAAAAAAUUAGCCAGGCGUGGCAGCGUGCGCCUGUAGUCCCCGCGACUUGGAGGCUGAUGCAGGAGAAUCGCUUUAACCCGGGAGGCAGAGGUUGCAGUGAGCCGAGAUCGAGCCACUGUACUCCAGACUGGGUGACAGAGCGACACUCUGUCUCAAAAAAAAAAAAAAGAUUUAACUGCCCCACUGGAUUUUGGAAUUGCAGGGGACCUUCAGCCCCUUCGUUUGUCCAGUUUCUCCCAUUUGGAAUGGGUAUAUCCAACGCCUGUACCCCAUUGUAUAUAGGAAGUAACUAACUUGCUUUUGAUUUUACAGGCUCACAGAAGGGACGUGCCUUGUCUCAGAUGAGAUUUUGGACUGUGGACUUUUGAGUUAAUGCUGAAAUGAGUUAAGACUUUGGGGGAUAGUUAGGAAGGCAUGACUAGUUUGAGGACAUUAUACUCAAUGAAAUAAGCCAGUCAAAAAGGAAAAAUAUGUAUUGUAUAAACUAACUUACAUUAAUCUACCACAUAGGAUUAAAACUGUUCACAGGAAUAUAAAAUAGAAUUUUUUAGAUA